AUGCUUGACGGGCAGUCGCCGCUUCUAAUCAGCGUGCCGCGCCAGCAGCUCCGUACCCUGCCGGGUUCCCACGUCUACCUGCAGCUGGGGGAAGAACUCUGCCAGCCCAGGGCAGGGGCGGGCACUCACUUGGACCAGGACCUGCCCGACGCCCCCGGUCCGCCGGGCGAACGGGUCGUCACUUUCUGUGAUCAGUUUGGGAAAAGGCUUGGGGGCCCUGCCACGGGCCAGUGUGGGAACCCAGGGUUCGAAUUCCCGCCCCGACGCUGCUUCCGGACCGAAAGCCCCCUGAACGCCUUGCCCCAAGUGCCCUGGGCCUUGGUUUCUCCAUCAGUGAAACAAUGAUGGGAAUCGCUUGACGUGAAGUGAGUGGAGGUGCUGGCACACUUCGAGUGAUUGCUAAGGGGAAGCCUUUGGUACUAGUUAGGAUAAUUAUUUUAAUUACAGUAUAGUUAGGGUAAUGAAUUCCAAAUACCAGUGUAGCAUCAUGUGCUUUAUAUACAAUAGGUAAUCGAUAAGUAAUAAAUAUUAAAUUUAUAUAACAGAAACAAUGGAUAAAUUUAUGUGCAUACAAAAUAUAUUUACCUAAUACAUUUAGAAGUAUAUAAUAUAUAAUAAACAUGUAAAAAAGUACAAUAAAAUAACAUCUCAUAAGCAAA